CCUAUUUUUUUUUUAGGAGUUUUAUAGUUUCAGGUCUAGGGUUUAGCAAUUUUAAUUUUUUUUGCAAACACCCUUUGACUUUUUAAUUCUCUAUAGUUUUAUUUCUAUUUCAUUAUGUUUUCCUCUUUAUUACUUCCUUUCUUCUUAUUUUGGGUUCUUUUUGCUUUUCUUUUUUUAGCUUCUUGAGAUGGGAGCUGAGUUAUUUUUAAUUAAAACUUCUUUUUUUAAAGUACAUUCAUUUAAAGCUAUAACUUUCUUUCUUUCUUUUUUUUUUUUUUUUUGAGACAAGAGUCUUGCUCUGUCGCCCAGGCUGGAGUGCAGUGGCACCAUCUCGGCUCACUGCCAACUCCGCCUCCCGGGUUCACGCCAUUCUCCUGCCUCAGCCUCCCGAGUAGCUGGGACUACAGGCACCUGCCACCAGGCCCAGCUAAUUUUUUGUAUUUUUAGUAGAGAUGGGGUUUCACCGUGUUAGCCAGGAUGGUCUCGAUCUCCUGACCUUGUGAUCCGCCCAGCUUGGCCUCCCAAAGUGCUGGGAUUACAGGCGUGAGCCACUGCGCCCGGCCAAAAGCUAUAACUUUCUUUCUAAGAACUGCCUUAUUACCGGCUGUAUUCAUUUGCUAGGGCUGCCAUAACAAAGUACCACACAAUGGGUGGCUGUAAACAACAGAAAUUUUUUCUUCAUAAUUCUGGAAGAUAGAAGUCCAAGAUCAAGGUUUCGGCAGGGUUGGUUUCUUCUGAGGCCUUUCUCCUUGGCUUAUAGCUGGUCAUCUCCUCCCUGUGUCUUCACAUGGUCUUCCCACCGGAAGUUUUUAUGUCCAAAUUUUCUCUUCUUACAAUGACACCAGUUAUAUUGGAGUAGGGCCCACUCUAAUGACCUCAUUUUUACUUAGUUAUCUCUUUAAAGACCUCACCUCCGAAGACAGUGACAUUCUAAGGUACUAGGGGUUAGGAUGUCAACAUACGAAUAUGGGAGACAAGGAAUAAUUCAGCCUGGAACAGCUCCAAGUCACAAAUUUGAUUUGCCUCUGCAACUUGACUCUCCUCUAGGAAGAGUACUCCAGAGAGCAGGGAUAUGUCACCAGGACUCCUGACAACCAGGAAGGAGGCAUUGAUGGCCUUCCGGGAUGUGGCUGUGGCCUUCACCCAGAAGGAGUGGAAGCUAUUGAGUUCUGCUCAGAGGACCCUGUACAGGGAGGUGAUGCUGGAGAACUACAGCCAUCUGGUCUCCCUGGGAAUUGCAUUUUCCAAACCAAAACUCAUCGAACAGCUGGAGCAAGGCGACGAACCUUGGAGAGAGGAGAACGAACAUCUUCUGGACCUUUGUCCAGAGCCUAGAACAGAAUUCCAGCCAAGUUUUCCCCACCUGGUGGCCUUUUCUAGCUCGCAGCUCCUCAGACAAUAUGCGCUAAGUGGCCAUCCCACACAGAUCUUCCCAAGCUCAUCUGCAGGAGGUGACUUCCAACUAGAAGCUCCAAGAUGCUCUAGUGAAAAAGGAGAAAGUGGAGAGACAGAAGGCCCCGACAGCUCAUUAAGAAAGAGGCCAAGCAGAAUUUCUAGGACAUUCUUCAGCCCACAUCAAGGUGACCCAGUAGAAUGGGUAGAAGGGAACAGAGAAGGAGGAACAGACCUUCGCCUGGCCCAAAGGAUGAGUCUUGGGGGGUCAGACACAAUGUUGAAGGGAGCAGACACUUCAGAAUCUGGAGCAGUCAUACGUGGAAACUAUAGACUGGGACUUAGCAAAAAGUCAAGCCUGUUCAGCCACCAGAAGCAUCAUGUGUGCCCUGAAUGCGGGAGAGGCUUUUGCCAGAGAUCAGACCUUAUCAAGCACCAGAGGACACACACCGGGGAGAAGCCAUACCUGUGUCCUGAGUGUGGGCGUCGGUUUAGCCAGAAGGCCUCCCUCUCCAUACACCAGAGGAAGCACUCGGGGGAGAAGCCGUAUGUGUGCAGGGAAUGUGGGCGACACUUCAGGUAUACAUCCUCUCUCACUAAUCACAAGAGGAUUCACUCCGGGGAGAGGCCCUUUGUAUGUCAGGAGUGUGGGCGAGGCUUUCGCCAGAAGAUAGCCCUCCUUCUACACCAGAGGACGCACUUGGAGGAGAAGCCCUUCGUGUGUCCUGAGUGUGGGAGAGGCUUUUGCCAGAAGGCAUCACUCCUCCAGCACCAGAGCUCACACACAGGGGAGAGGCCCUUCCUGUGCCUUGAGUGUGGGCGUAGCUUCAGGCAGCAGUCACUCCUCCUUAGUCACCAGGUCACACACUCAGGAGAGAAGCCUUAUGUCUGUGCUGAGUGUGGGCACAGCUUUCGCCAAAAGGUCACUCUCAUCAGGCACCAGAGGACACACACAGGGGAGAAGCCUUACCUGUGCCCCCAGUGUGGGCGGGGUUUUAGCCAGAAGGUCACCCUCAUUGGACACCAGAGGACACACACAGGGGAGAAGCCCUACCUGUGCCCUGAUUGUGGGCGUGGCUUUGGUCAGAAGGUCACCCUCAUCAGACACCAGAGGACACACACAGGGGAGAAGCCUUAUCUGUGCCCCAAGUGUGGGCGUGCAUUUGGCUUUAAGUCGCUCCUCACCCGACACCAGAGGACACACUCAGAGGAGGAGCUUUACGUAGACAGGGUGUGUGGACAAGGACUUGGCCAGAAGUCACACCUUAUCUCUGACCAAAGGACACACUCAGGAGAGAAGCCCUGCAUUUGCGAUGAAUGUGGGCGCGGCUUUGGCUUUAAGUCUGCCCUCAUCCGACAUCAGCGGACCCAUUCUGGGGAGAAGCCGUAUGUCUGCAGGGAGUGUGGGCGUGGCUUUAGCCAGAAGUCUCACUUGCAUAGACACAGGAGGACCAAGUCUGGUCAUCAGCUCCUACCCCAAGAGGUCUUCUGACCUUUCCUUUCCCCGUGAGUGUGAAGCUGGCAGAAAUCACUAGUAAAUGCUUCAGUUUCCUGAAAUGGAAUGGAAAAAAAAAAAUGUUGCUUUCUUUCAUCGAUCAUGAGAUAGUUGAUUUUUGGUUUACUUUCUAUAUUCACAAUUUGUCUUGGCUUGCUAGGGGUUCCAUAACAAAGUACCCCAGGCUGGGUGAUUUUGACAACGGAAAUAUAUUUUCAUAUUUAUGGAGGCUGGAAGUCCCAGAUGAACGUAUUGGUAGGUUUGGCUGCUGCUUAAGCCUCUCUGUUUGGCUUGCGGAUGGCUGCUUUCUGGCCACGUCCUCACGUGGGCUUUUUUCUGUGUGUAUGCUUUCCUGGUGUGGCUUCCUCCUCUUCUAGGGACACCAGUCAUUUUGGAUAGAGCCACAGCCACAUGGCCUCGUUUAACCUUAAUAACCUUCCUAAAGGCCUUAUCUCU